GCCUCCGAGGGCUCCGGAGCGGCGACUGGCGAGCCAUGGCGCUGGGGCUGCAGCGCGCAAGGCCGGCCCUUUCCUGUGGAGUCAUCUCACCGCCGUGCGCACCCACUCGUAACUCGCACCCGGGUCCUGGCUGCACCGCAUCCCCUCCUGCACCCCCUGGAUGGCCCUUCAGCCAACGGGGGCCUGGGCGAUGGUCGACCACGGAGCUGCGCAAGGAAAAGUCCCGGGAUGCGGCCCGCAGCCGGCGCAGCCAGGAGACCGAGGUGCUGUACCAGCUGGCUCACACGCUGCCCUUCGCCCGCGGCGUCAGCGCCCACCUGGACAAGGCCUCUAUCAUGCGCCUCACCAUCAGCUACCUGCGCAUGCACCGCCUCUGCGCCGCAGGGGAGUGGAACCAGGUGGGAGCAGGGGGAGAACCACUGGAUGCCUGCUACCUGAAGGCCCUGGAGGGCUUCGUCAUGGUGCUCACCGCCGAGGGAGACAUGGCUUACCUGUCGGAGAAUGUCAGCAAACACCUGGGCCUCAGUCAGCUGGAGCUCAUUGGACACAGCAUCUUUGAUUUCAUCCACCCCUGUGACCAAGAGGAGCUUCAGGACGCCCUGACCCCCCAGCAGACCCUGUCCAGGAGGAAGGUGGAGGCCCCCACGGAGCGGUGCUUCUCCUUGCGCAUGAAGAGUACACUCACCAGCCGCGGGCGCACCCUCAACCUCAAGGCGGCCACCUGGAAGGUGCUGAACUGCUCUGGACAUAUGAGGGCCUACAAGCCACCUGCGCAGACUUCUCCAGCUGGGAGCCCUGACUCAGAGCCCCCGCUGCAGUGCCUGGUGCUCAUCUGCGAAGCCAUCCCCCACCCAGGCAGCCUGGAGCCCCCACUGGGCCGAGGGGCCUUCCUCAGCCGCCACAGCCUGGACAUGAAGUUCACCUACUGUGACGACAGGAUUGCAGAAGUGGCUGGCUAUAGUCCCGAUGACCUGAUCGGCUGUUCCGCCUACGAGUACAUCCACGCGCUGGACUCCGAUGCGGUCAGCAAGAGCAUCCACACCUUGCUGAGCAAGGGCCAGGCAGUAACAGGGCAGUAUCGCUUCCUGGCCCGGAGUGGUGGCUACCUGUGGACCCAGACCCAGGCCACAGUGGUGUCAGGGGGACGGGGCCCCCAGUCGGAGAGUAUCGUCUGUGUCCAUUUUUUAAUCAGCCAGGUGGAAGAGACCGGAGUGGUGCUGUCCCUGGAGCAAACGGAGCAACACUCUCGCAGACCCAUUCAGCGGGGCGCCCCCUCUCAGAAGGACACCCCUAACCCUGGGGACAGCCUUGACACCCCUGGCCCCCGGAUCCUUGCCUUCCUGCACCCGCCUUCCCUGAGCGAGGCUGCCCUGGCCGCUGACCCCCGCCGUUUCUGCAGCCCUGACCUCCGUCGCCUCCUGGGACCCAUCCUGGAUGGGGCUUCAGUAGCAGCCACUCCCAGCACCCCGCUGGCCACACGGCACCCCCAAAGUCCUCUUUCGGCUGAUCUCCCAGAUGAACUACCUGUGGGCACCGAGAAUGUGCACAGACUCUUCACCUCCGGGAAAGACACUGAGGCAGUGGAGACAGAUUUAGAUAUAGCUCAGAUGAGGAAACUGAAGCUCAGACUGUUGACCACAGGCACAGAACUCAGAAGUGAUGGUGCUGGGACUUCAGCCAAGGUCCACCCAAGUCCAAGGCUCAUCCUCUUACCUCCCUCCUGCCCUCCGCAGGAUGCUGAUGCUCUGGAUUUGGAGAUGCUGGCCCCCUACAUCUCCAUGGAUGAUGACUUCCAGCUCAACGCCAGCGAGCAGCUACCCAGGGCCUACCACAGACCUCUGGGGGCUGUCCCCCGGCCCCGUGCUCGGAGCUUCCAUGGCCUGUCACCUCCAGCCCUUGAGCCCUCCCUGCUACCCCGCUGGGGGAGUGACCCCCGGCUGAGCUGCUCCAGCCCUUCCAGAGGGGACCCCUCAGCAUCCUCUCCCAUGGCUGGGGCUCGGAAGAGGACCCUGGCCCAGAGCUCAGAGGACGAGGACGAGGGAGUGGAGCUGCUGGGAGUGAGACCUCCCAAAAGGUCCCCCAGCCCAGAACACGAAAACUUUCUGCUCUUUCCUCUCAGCCUGAGUUUCCUUCUGACAGGAGGACCAGCCCCAGGGAGCCUGCAGGACCCCAGCACCCCACUCCUGAACCUGAAUGAGCCCCUGGGCCUGGGCCCCUCACUGCUCUCUCCGUACUCAGACGAGGACACUACCCAGCCCGGGGGCCCCUUCCAGCCAAGGGCAGGCUCAGCCCAGGCUGACUGAGCCGGCUCCUCUCCCCAUCUGCCUUCUCCUCCCCCAGAAAGGACCUCAACCACACUCCACGCCGGCAGCCAACGCACAGGAUGGGGGCGCCAGGAGAGGGGCCCCUCUCUCCUCUAUGUACCCCCUGCCCACCUCGGGCCUACCUCAGCCCUCACCCCUCUGCCUGCUCCCAAUCUGGGGGCUCUCUGGGGUGGUCUCAGCUCAGUGACCUCUGGGAGGUGGUCCCUGGCCCCCUCCUCCUUCUCUCAGGAUUUCUCUUGGGGUUCUCAAUACUUGGUUACCUCAUUAUCCCUUUCUCUGCCUCUCUUGGCUUUAUUUUGGGGAAUCAGGGGUGAGGAGGGUUGGGGGGGUCAUAUCUGUGUUUCCAGGUUCUGGGGAGAACAAUGAUCCACGGGUCAACGUGAUCACAUUUCCUUCUAUCCUUCUUGUAUUAUUAUUUUUAUUUUUGUCAAUUUCAUGAUAUGGUUUUUAAUCAUGAUGAAUUGCCUGGGGUCUGUAAGAAUGUGGGACUCUGAUCUUCCCCCUCUUCAGGUGUCAGUGCGGAGAGGCUCUGGGCCAGACCUCACCCCCAGUGACUUCCGAUUGAGGCCAAAGACCCCAAGCUGCCCGCCAGCUCUGACUGCCCCUUGCGCUCUGGGCUUCCUGCCGCCCCCAGCUUUGCCUGGACACUGACUUCAUUCAUGGUCCUCCUACUUCAGGGGCAGCCUCCCAGUUCCUCUGCUUCCAAACUAUGCAACCUCCAACCUGCUCCAGUUCCAGACUGUAUAACCUCUGACCUGCACUGGUUCUAGACCACACAACCUCCAAUGUGGUCUGCUUUAGAUCACCUUCUUCUUCUUCCUUCUUCCUCUUCCUCUUCCUCCUGCUCCUCUUCCUCUUCUUCUUCUUUUUUUUUUUUGACAGAGUCUUGCUCUGUCACCCAGGCUGGAGUGCAGUGGCGCGAUUUCAGCUUACUGCAGCCUCCGCGCCCUGGGUUCAAGUGAUUCUCCUGCCUCAACUUCCCAAAUAGCCGGGACUACGGGCAUGUGCCACAUUGCCCGGCUAAUUUUUGUAUUUUUAGUAGAGAUGGGGUUUCACCACGUUGUCCAGUCUGGUCUCGAACUCCUGACCUCAAGUGCUCCACCUGCCUCAGCCUUCCAAAGUGCUGGGAUUACAGGCGUGAGCCACUGCACCCGGCUAGAACUCACUUUCUCCAAAUCCCUCUGCUUCGAAUUUCACCGUCUUCAGCUCUUUCUAGUUCUGGGCCUCACCAGCCUCUCAUUCUGCCUGUUUUCAAACCUUACGAUCCCCAAAAAUUGUCUGGUUCUGGGCCUCUAACUCCCUCUGGCUCUAUAGUCUAUGACUACCAGAUUCUUUUGGUUCUAGAAUUCACUAACUUCCUCUGGUUCUAGACCUCUUCCUAUAAAUUAAUCCCUCUUGUUUUAGAUCUCACACCCUCCAACGCCCUCCGGUUCCAGAUCUUAUAUUCAGUGAUUUCCUCUGGUUCUGGACCCCACAACUCCAAGCUUCCUAUUGGUUCCAGUUCUCCUGAUCGGUAAUACAUUUGGUUCCAAAUCCAGACCUCUUAAUCUCUCUCUUUUUUUUUUUUUUUUUUUGAGACAGAGUCCCACUCUGUCACCCAGGCUGGAGUACAGUGGCUCAAUCUCGGCUCACUGCAGCCUCCACCUCCUGGGUUCAAGCAAUUCUUGGGCCUCAGCCUCCCAAAUAGCUGGGAUUACAGGCAUGUGCCACCACGCCCAGCUAAGUUUUAUAUUUUUAGUAGAGACAGUGUUUCACCAUGUUGGCCAGGCUGGUCUUGAACUCCCGACCUCAACUGAUCCACCCGCCUCAGCCUCCCAAAGUGCUGAAAUUACAGGAGUGAGCCUGGCCAGACUUCUUAAUUUCUAAAUCACUUUUGUUUUAGACCUUAUGAGGCUCAGCUUAUUCUUCUGCAGUUCUCUAUAACCAAGACUCAUUUUCUCUCAUCAAAAACAAGUACAGAGAGUUUGAUGUGUUUAUCUCUUUUUUCUUCCUCUUCUUUUUUUUUUUUUUCUUUUUUGAGAUGGAGUCUCUCUCUGUUGCCCAGGCUGGAGUAUAAUGGUGCCAUCUAGGCUCACUGCAACCUCCGCCUCCUGAUUCAAGUGAUUCUCCUGCCUCAGCCUCCUAAAUUGGUGGGAUUACAGGAGCCCACCACCACAUCCGGCUACCUUUGUGUAUUUUUUAGUAGAGACGGGGUUUUGCCAAGUUGGAGGGGCUGGUCUUGAACUCUUGACCUCAGAUGAUCCACCCGCCUCAGCCUCCCAAAGUGCUGGGAUUACAGGCAUAAGCCACCGUGCCCGACCCUGUCCUUAUCUUAUAAUAACCAGUUCUUCUAGAACCAGACGAUGCUCUAGUUCUCCUAGAUUCUGAACCUCAUGACCUGUACCACUCACUAGUUCCAGACUACACAACUUCUAGAAGGUGCCACCUCCAGGGUCCUGAUUCAAGAUCUGGUGAUCUGCUGUUUCUCUGGUUCUAGAACUGACUUACAAGUGCCUUCUGAUUCUAGACCUCAUUCCGUAAGUUCCCUUGGCUCUAGACUUCAUCAUUUCCAGCUCCUCCUCACUCAAGAUCUGACUCCAAAUUACCCUGGGUCUAGAAUUCAGCCUUCAAAUAUCUUCUGAUUUUAGACUUUGCCUUAUACAUUUCUCUGGUUUUAGAUCUUACCACCCUCAACUCCUUCUGAUUCUAGAUCUUAUGGUUCCCAAAUCUCUCUGGUUCUAGAACUCAGAUUUUAGGCUUUUGUUUUUCCUUUUUUUUGUUAAAAAAAAAAAAAUAGAGACGGGGUUUCACCAUGUUGCCCAGGCUGGUCGCGAACUACUGAGCUCAAGCAAUUCUCCCUCCUUGGCCUCACCAAAGUGCUGGGACUACAGGCAUGAGCCACUGAGCCCAGCCAGGCUUUUUCUAAUUCUAUGCUUUAUUCUAUAAAUUCCUCUGCUUCUAAGCCUCACAGCUUCCAACUGCCUUUGAUUUCAGAUCCAAAUUCCUCUGAUUCUAUAAUUCAGCCUCCAAAUGCUUCUGAUUCUGGAAUCUAGACUUUUCCCUAAAGAUUCCUCUGGUUCUGAAUCUUAUAACCUCAACUCCCUAAUUCCAGACCCCAGCCUCCUAAAUCUAUUCUGGGCUUCCCACCCCACUGAACUUACCCAAUUCCUUCUUUCAGUCUUAAGUUUUCCCAUUCUAAACCCCUACCCUCUAGGCUGUGCUGCUCCUGGACUUCAUGCCUCUCCAUUCUCAUUGCCUACAAUCUCUGUGCCCCAGAACCCCCUCCACUUCCCACCCCAGCCCUCCAGACAUGCACUUACCUUGACUUUACCCCACAUGUUUGGGGCACCUGGGGCUCCCUCACCCCUUGGGUGGUUUGCAAUCUGAAGACUUCUCCAGCCACACAGGCACAUGCACAGGCACGGUGCUGUCUGCAUAUUGCCAGGUGGGGAGAGAAGCCAGGACCCCUCAGCUGUCUGCCACCAUCUAUGUGCCUCCCUUACCCCCCAGCUUUCUUUCUACAGAUGGUGCUACUCUUGGUCUCCCACAGGAAAAGGCCUCCCCCCUUCUUAGCCCCAUUUACCCCGUUUGUGGAAGGCACUGCUCGCUCUGUUUUGUCAGAGAGUGGCCUAUCCAGAUUGGUGCUAUGGGGGGGUCUGACCCCUCCCUCCUCCCUCUGGAGGUGAUGUGGGCCCUCAAUGGAGGGAAUUGUGCUGGGCUAGGGAAAGGGGAGGGACUAGACUGGCCACACUGGCUCUGAAACUCACCAAUCUCUAUACACCAUAAAGACCUCACCUUGGUAGGCACCAGA